GAGCGUAUUUCUGUUUCUUAUGCCUUGCUAAGAAUACUUAUUUGGCUUCCAAUAAAAUUACUCUAGAAAACCCUAAGAGAUUUGUUUAAAUUGCUUAUUAGUAUAUGUUAUAAAAUUGACAGGGCAGUGACUAAAAAAGAUUAGAAGUUCACAAACUGUGGGAUUUAAUUUUCUUUUGGGUAAGCUUAGCAAAAACAAUAGGAAAUACCCCAGUGGCAUAGAGAGCAGAAUUCUACAUAGGGUACACUCCCUGCCCCAGCCUUGUUCAAAUUUACUGUUUUUGGAGGCCUUAUUUAGGUCUGGCCCCACCCUGGAGUCUUGCCUCACAGAACUGAUUAGAAGAGAUGAGAGUACUGGGUGGUGAAUCCUGCAGCCUUUCUAGAGCCAGUGCUCACGGUAUUCUGAAACCUAAAAGCAGAUAAAUGGAAAAAAUAAAGUAUGUAUUUUAGGGUCUUAAUUUUUAGUUUUUUUAUUAAAACCAGUGCUUGCAGAGACAUUCCAUUUACCAACCUGUUUUCUAUUCUUGGAGAUGUUGUUGCUCUGCAAGUCAGAAAAAAGUAAAUAUAAACACAAUAAAAAUUUCUCUAAGCUGCAUUAAAGUUUUUCUUUCUGUAUCCCUCUCCUCUGUCUAUAUUUAGCUUUAAUUCUAUACAUUUUUUAAAAAAAUCAGUGACAGAGAAACAAAAGAAAUAAAAAUGCUGGGCCCUUUUUCUAAAUCCAGGGAAUUAUUAAACACUUAAUACCAGCUCCCAAGGUGCUAUGAGGAUUAAAUCAUGUAAUGUGUUAUUCCCAGCAAAGUGCUCUGUAACAGUCCCUUCAGCACAUAGUACCUGCUUAAUAAUCAUUGCAUUAGUACAUGUGAAAAUGUUAUUUUUCUUUUCUUUUUUCUUGAGACAGAGUGUUGCUGUUGUCGUCUAGGCUGGAGUGCAAUGGUGGGAUCUCGACUUACUGCAACCUCUUCCUCCUAAGUUCAAGUGAUUCUCCUACCUCGGCCUCCUGAGUAGCUGGGAUUACAGGCACCCGCCACCAUGCCCAACUAAUUUUUGUAUUUUUAUUAGAGACAGGGUUUCACCAUGUUGGCCAGGUUGGUCUUGAACUCCUGACCUCAGGUGAUCCACCUGUUUUGGACCCCCAAAGUGCCCGGCCUGUUUUUCAAAUGCAGAUUUAUUCAGACAUAGCUGCCUUCUGUUUGUUCUGUAAACUUAAAAGAGCCAGCAAAAAAUAUGAAAAUUGAUUAUCUUCAUUUGUCCUAGAAGUAUUUGUAUUUUGACAAGAGUGCUGAGUGUAAGGAACUCUGCUGUGUCUGCUUUCUCUAACUAAUGCUAAUAAUGAGCCCAAGGGGAGCAACAUCAGCUUUGACAGGAGACUUGUUUAAAACUCCCAUUCAUGAACCCUUUCCAAACCUGCAGUAUCACAUUACAUAGGGGACCACUGACAUUUAUGGAUGUGGCCAUAGAGUUCUCUUUGGAGGAGUGGCAGUGCCUGGACACUGCACAGCGGAAUGUAUAUAGGCAUGUGAUGUUAGAGAACUACAGAAACCUGGUUUUCUUGGACCUGAUUACCUGUCUGGAACAAGGAAAAGAGCCCUGGAAUAUGAAGAGACAUGAGAUGGUGGUAGCCAAACAUUCAGCUGUAGCAUUUACCUUUGAUCUCAGUGGACUCAACAUUUUGUCAUUCCAAAGUAUCCUGCCAUUUGUUUCAGCACUUUAUGUCAUGGGAAACAGAAACCAGUGUCUGCAAAAGCACCUAGAAGCCAGAAAUAAAGAUCUCUGUGUUCUCGUUUUGCCCAAGACCUUUGGCUAGAGCAGAACAUAAAAGAUUCUUUCCAAAAAGUGACACUGAGCAGAUAUGGAAAAUAUGGACAUAAGAAUUUACAGUUAAGAAAAGGCUGUAAAAGUGUGGAUGAGUGUAAGGGACACCAAGGAGGUUUUAAUGGACUUAACCAAUGUUUGAAAAUUACCACAAGCAAAAUAUUUCAAUGUAAUAAAUAUGUAAAAGUCAUGCAUAAAUUUUCAAAUUCAAAUAGACACAAGAUAAGACAUACUGAAAAUAAACAUUUCAGAUGUAAAGAAUGUGACAAAUCACUUUGCAUGCUUUCACGCCUAACUCAACAUAAAAAAAUUCAUACUAGAGAGAAUUUCUACAAAUGUGAAGAGUGUGGAAAAACCUUUAACUGGUCCACAAACCUUUCUAAACCUAAGAAAAUUCAUACUGGAGAAAAACCCUACAAAUGUGAAGUAUGUGGAAAAGCCUUUCACCAAUCCUCAAUCCUUACUAAACAUAAGAUAAUUCGUACUGGAGAAAAACCCUAUAAAUGUGCACACUGUGGCAAAGCCUUUAAACAGUCCUCACACCUUACUAGACAUAAGAUAAUUCAUACUGAAGAGAAACCCUACAAAUGUGAACAAUGUGGCAAGGUCUUUAAGCAGUCCCCAACCCUUACUAAACAUCAGAUAAUUUAUACUGGAGAGGAACCAUACAAAUGUGAGGAAUGUGGCAAAGCUUUUAACCUAUCUUAACAACUUACUGAACAUAAGAAAAUUUACACUAGAGAGAAAGCCUACAAAUGUGAAGAAUGUGGCAAAGCCUUUAACCAGUUUUCAACCCUUAUUACACAUAAGAUAAUUCAUAGCGGAGAGAAACCCCACAAAUGUGAAGAAUGUGGCAGAGCUUUUAACCAGUCCGCAAAGCUCACUGAACAUAAGUUAAUUCAUACUGGAGAAAAACCCUACAAAUGUAAAGAAUGUGGAAAAGCUUUUCACCGAUACUCAAUCCUUAGUACACAUAAGAAAAUUCAUACUGGGGAGAAACCCCACAAAUGUGGAGAAUGCGGAAAAGCCUUUAACUGGUCCUCAACUCUUAUUACACAUAAGAUAAUUCACAGUGGAGAAAAACCCUACAAAUGUGAAGAAUGUGGCAAAGCUUUUAACCAGUCCUCACACCUUAUGAGACAUAAGAAAAUUCAUAGUAAAGAGAAACCCUACAAAUGUGAACAGUGUGGCAAGGUCUUUAAGAAGUCCUCAACUCUUACUGCACAUAAGAUCAUUCAUACUGGAGAGAAACCUUACAAAUGUGAGGAAUGUGGCAAAGGUUUUAGCCAACUCUCAAACCUUACUAAACACAAGAAGAUUCAUACUAGAGAGAAACCCUACAAAUGUGAAGAAUGUGGCAUAUCUUUUAACCAGUUCUCACAACUUGCUAUACAUAAGAUGAUUCACACUUGAAUGAAACCCUACAAAUGUGAACGAUGUGGCAGUUGUUUUAACUAGUUCUCGAACUUUACUAUGCAUAAGAAAAUUCAAACUGGAGAGAAACUCUACAAAUGUGAAGAAUGUGGCAAAGCUUUUAACCAAGUCUCAACACUUACUAUACAUAAGAUAAUUUAUACUGGAGCAAAACCUUGGAAAUUCAAAGAAUGUGGUAAAACUUACAAUCCUCAAAACUUCUUACACCUAAAAUUCAUGCAGGAGAGAAACACCACAAAUGUGAAAAAUUUGGUAAAUUCUUUAACAAGUCUUCAACCCUUUCUGCACAUAAUAUAAUUCAUACUGGAGAGAAACCCCACAAAUAUGAAGAAUGUGGUAAUGCUUUUAACCAAUUCUCAAAUCUUACUAAACAAAAUUAAUACUGAAAAUGUUACAAACCAGAAAAAUGUGAAAAUGAUUUUAACAAAACCUUCAAAUUUUUCUAAACAUAAAGGAAAUCAUACUGGUAAGAAAUUAUAAAAAUGUGAAGAAUGUGACAAAGCCUUUAAAUGGUUGUCACACUUGAUUGUAGGUAAGAUAAUUCAUACUGGCAGAAACUCCCAGAAGUGUGAAGAAUAUGGCAAAACUUUAAUUCCUAUACCUUAUUGCACAGGAAAGCAUUUAUACUUCAGAAAAUGUUGUACUGAUAUAAAGAAUGUAGAAAAGCCAUUAAUAUGUGCUUACAUCUUAUUCAACAUUAGAGAGUUAGUACUUAAUAAAAGCAUUAUAAAUGCAAUUACUGUCAAAACUCA